AGUCGCGCCGGGGCUGAGCGCCGAGCGGGGCGGCGGCGGGGCGGGCGGCGGCUCCUCGGCGGCUCCGCGGCGCCCGGGCCGCGCGCCGCCAUGCUGGGCCUGGACGCGUGCGAGCUGGGGGCGCAGCUGCUGGAGCUGCUCCGGCUGGCGCUGUGCGCCCGAGUCCUCCUGGCUGACAAGGAGGGUGGGCCGCCGGCAGUGGACGAGGUGUUGGAUGAGGCUGUGCCCGAGUACCGGGCGCCGGGGAGGAAGAGCCUCUUGGAGAUCCGGCAGCUGGACCCGGACGACAGGAGCCUGGCCAAGUACAAGCGGGUGCUGCUGGGGCCCCUGCCACCGGCCGUGGACCCAAGCCUGCCCAAUGUGCAGGUGACCAGGCUGACACUCCUGUCGGAACAGGCUCCGGGGCCCGUCGUCAUGGAUCUCACAGGGGACCUGGCUGUUCUGAAGGACCAGGUGUUUGUCCUGAAGGAAGGUGUUGAUUACAGAGUGAAGAUCUCCUUCAAGGUCCACAGGGAGAUUGUCAGCGGCCUCAAGUGUCUGCACCACACCUACCGCCGGGGCCUGCGCGUGGACAAGACCGUCUACAUGGUGGGCAGCUAUGGCCCGAGCGCCCAGGAGUAUGAGUUUGUGACUCCGGUGGAGGAAGCGCCGAGGGGUGCGCUGGUGCGGGGCCCCUAUCUGGUGGUGUCCCUCUUCACCGACGAUGACAGGACGCACCACCUGUCCUGGGAGUGGGGUCUCUGCAUCUGCCAGGACUGGAAGGACUGAACCCCCAGUCCGUGUCUCCCCUACCUCCCUCAGUUGUUGCACAGGGACCCCCAAGCAUCCCCAGCACCCCCCGUGAGUGACCAGACCCUCCCCUGCUGCCCCUGCUGCCCCUGCUGCCCCUGCUCUGUCCCGGGACCCCCUGGCCUGGCGCUGUCCCCUGAGCUGUCCCAUUAAACAUGGCCCUGUCUCUCUCGGU